GGCCUCCUCUCCCUCCUUGCUCUCUCUGGCACCCCAAUUCUUCCUCCUCUCCCCCAGAUGUGUCUCCCCUCCCCCUCGUCUUCCCCCUGUCUCUUUCUCCCUCUUGUAACUUUGUCUCUGUCAUCAGUUGUCUCUUUCAUCAUUUAUAACUGAAGAUGGAAACUAAAGAAGUUUCCUUUCUCUGUGUCUGGCCCCAUCCCUGUUUCUUUCUUCUCAUCUGCCUCCCUGUGGUCUCUCCCCAUCUUCCCAUCUCUCUCUGUCUCUCCCCAUCUCCCCGUCUCUCCCUUUCUCUGCCAUCUCCCUAUGUCUCUCCCAUCUCCCUAUGCCUCUCCCAUCUCCAUCUGUCUGACUCUCUGUAUUCUUCAGCCCCUCUCUGUGACUUAUGAAGUUCCCUCCCUCUCUACUGCCAAUGGGGAAGCCAGAGGGGGCUGAGGGUGGGGGGCCGAGGGGCCCAGUGUGGGGGCCCCAACCCAGGCCCAGAGCCCAGCCUGGCAGCCUCUCUCAGAUCUGGGACGACCAUUUCCUUUUUCAACCCUGGAGUCCACUCGAGUUACUCGGGAGCUCAGGAUGGUGCAGACCAGGGGAAGGAGGUGACUCUCCCGGCGUGUGGCUGGUCGUCGGUGGGGCCUUUGGACAGGUCUCAGACCCUGGGCCUGGGCUCUGUGGGGCUCUAUGCAAGUUGCUUACCCUCUCUGAGCCUCAGUUUUCCCUGCUGUAAAAUGAGGGUACAUACAGAAUCCAGCUCAGGUUGUAAGGAUCAAAUACGUAAAAGGUGUGGAGAGUUUAGAGCCAAGCCCUACACACGCUCAGAGGCCCCACUGGACCCUCGGCUCUUCCUUGGACUUCUUGUGUGUUCUGUGAGCUUCGCUGGAUUCAGGGUCUUGGGCAUCAGAGGUGAGAGGGUGGGAAGGUCCGCCGCGAUGGGGAAGCCCUGGCUGCGUGCGCUACAGCUGCUGCUCCUGCUGGGCGCGUCGUGGGCGCGGGCGGGCGCCCCGCGCUGCACCUACACCUUCGUGCUGCCCCCGCAGAAGUUCACGGGCGCUGUGUGCUGGAGCGGCCCCGCAUCCACGCGGGCGACGCCCGAGGCCGCCAACGCCAGCGAGCUGGCGGCGCUGCGCAUGCGCGUCGGCCGCCACGAGGAGCUGUUACGCGAGCUGCAGAGGCUGGCGGCGGCCGACGGCGCCGUGGCCGGCGAGGUGCGCGCGCUGCGCAAGGAGAGCCGCGGCCUGAGCGCGCGCCUGGGCCAGUUGCGCGCGCAGCUGCAGCACGAGGCGGGGCCCGGGGCGGGCCCGGGGGCGGAUCUGGGGGCGGAGCCUGCCGCGGCGCUGGCGCUGCUCGGGGAGCGCGUGCUCAACGCGUCCGCCGAGGCUCAGCGCGCAGCCGCCCGGUUCCACCAGCUGGACGUCAAGUUCCGCGAGCUGGCGCAGCUCGUCACCCAGCAGAGCAGUCUCAUCGCCCGCCUGGAGCGCCUGUGCCCGGGAGGCGCGGGCGGGCAGCAGCAGGUCCUGCCGCCACCCCCACUGGUGCCUGUGGUUCCGGUCCGUCUUGUGGGUAGCACCAGUGACACCAGUAGGAUGCUGGACCCAGCCCCAGAGCCCCAGAGAGACCAGACCCAGAGACAGCAGGAGCCCAUGGCUUCUCCCAUGCCUGCAGGUCACCCUGCGGUCCCCACCAAGCCUGUGGGCCCGUGGCAGGAUUGUGCAGAGGCCCGCCAGGCAGGCCAUGAACAGAGUGGAGUGUAUGAACUGCGAGUGGGCCGUCACGUAGUGUCAGUAUGGUGUGAGCAGCAACUGGAGGGUGGAGGCUGGACUGUGAUCCAGCGGAGGCAAGAUGGUUCAGUCAACUUCUUCACUACCUGGCAGCACUAUAAGGCGGGCUUUGGGCGGCCAGACGGAGAAUACUGGCUGGGCCUUGAACCCGUGUAUCAGCUGACCAGCCGUGGGGACCAUGAGCUGCUGGUUCUCCUGGAGGACUGGGGGGGCCGUGGAGCACGUGCCCACUAUGAUGGCUUCUCCCUGGAACCCGAGAGCGACCACUACCGCCUGCGGCUUGGCCAGUACCAUGGUGAUGCUGGAGACUCUCUUUCCUGGCACAAUGACAAGCCCUUCAGCACCGUGGAUAGGGACCGAGACUCCUAUUCUGGUAACUGUGCCCUGUACCAGCGGGGAGGCUGGUGGUACCAUGCCUGUGCCCACUCCAACCUCAACGGUGUGUGGCACCACGGCGGCCACUACCGAAGCCGCUACCAGGAUGGUGUCUACUGGGCUGAGUUUCGUGGUGGGGCAUAUUCUCUCAGGAAGGCCGCCAUGCUCAUUCGGCCCCUGAAGCUGUGACUCUGUGUUCCUCUGUCCCCUAGGCCCUAGAGGACAUUGGUCAGCAGGAGCCCAAGUUGUUCUGGCCACACCUUCUUUGUGGCUCAGUGCCAAUGUGUCCCACAGAACUUCCCACUGUGGAUCUGUGACCCUGGGCGCUGAAAAUGGGACCCAGGAAUCCCCCCCGUCAAUAUCUUGGCCUCAGAUGGCUCCCCAAGGUCAUUCAUAUCUCGGUUUGAGCUCAUAUCUUAUAAUAACACAAAGUAGCCACA